CUUUCCAGGUGUUAGUCGAAACCUCGUGGUGCGACCCUGGUCGUCCCAAACCCCCUAGGCCUUAAUCCUGGGGCGGUGGGGGCGGGGAGGCCGUGAGCACGGCUUCCGCUCCUCCAAUCCGCCAGAGGGCGCAGCGGCCGGCCUCUCCCUUCCCGGGGUUCUUCGCGCCGGGCCCCUUCCGCGUGGACGGGGCUCAUCUGCCGCCGCCGCCGCGCUGAGGAGAGUUCGCCGCCGUCGCCGCCCGUGAGGAUCUGAGAGCCAUGUCGGCCAGCAGCCUCUUGGAGCAGAGACCAAAAGGUCAAGGAAACAAAGUACAAAAUGGAUCUGUACAUCAAAAGGAUGGAUUAAACGAUGAUGAUUUUGAACCUUACUUGAGUCCACAGGCAAGGCCCAAUAAUGCAUAUACUGCCAUGUCAGAUUCCUACUUACCCAGUUACUACAGUCCCUCCAUUGGCUUCUCCUAUUCUUUGGGUGAAGCUGCUUGGUCUACGGGGGGUGACACAGCCAUGCCCUACUUAACUUCUUAUGGACAGCUGAGCAACGGAGAGCCCCACUUCCUACCAGAUGCAAUGUUUGGGCAACCAGGAGCCCUAGGUAGCACUCCAUUUCUUGGUCAGCAUGGUUUUAAUUUCUUUCCCAGUGGGAUUGACUUCUCAGCAUGGGGAAAUAACAGUUCUCAGGGACAGUCUACUCAGAGCUCUGGAUAUAGUAGCAAUUAUGCUUAUGCACCUAGCUCCUUAGGUGGAGCCAUGAUUGAUGGACAGUCAGCUUUUGCCAAUGAGACCCUCAAUAAGGCUCCUGGCAUGAAUACUAUAGACCAAGGGAUGGCAGCACUGAAGUUGGGUAGCACAGAAGUUGCAAGCAAUGUUCCAAAAGUUGUAGGUUCUGCUGUUGGUAGCGGGUCCAUUACUAGUAACAUCGUGGCUUCCAAUAGUUUGCCUCCAGCCACCAUUGCUCCUCCAAAACCAGCAUCUUGGGCUGAUAUUGCUAGCAAGCCUGCAAAACAGCAACCUAAACUGAAGACCAAGAAUGGCAUUGCAGGGUCAAGUCUUCCGCCACCCCCGAUAAAGCAUAACAUGGAUAUUGGAACUUGGGAUAACAAGGGUCCCGUUGCAAAAGCCCCCUCACAGGCUUUGGUUCAGAAUAUAGGUCAGCCAACCCAGGGGUCUCCUCAGCCUGUAGGUCAGCAGGCUAACAAUAGCCCACCAGUGGCUCAGGCAUCAGUAGGGCAACAGACACAGCCAUUGCCUCCACCUCCACCACAGCCUGCCCAGCUUUCAGUCCAGCAACAGGCAGCUCAGCCAACCCGCUGGGUAGCACCUCGGAACCGUGGCAGUGGGUUCGGUCAUAAUGGGGUGGAUGGUAAUGGAGUAGGACAGUCUCAGGCUGGUUCUGGAUCUACUCCUUCAGAACCCCACCCAGUGUUGGAGAAGCUUCGGUCCAUUAAUAACUAUAACCCCAAAGAUUUUGACUGGAAUCUGAAACAUGGCCGGGUUUUCAUCAUUAAGAGCUACUCUGAGGACGAUAUUCACCGUUCCAUUAAGUAUAAUAUUUGGUGCAGCACAGAGCAUGGUAACAAGAGACUGGAUGCUGCUUAUCGUUCCAUGAACGGGAAAGGCCCCGUUUACUUACUUUUCAGUGUCAACGGCAGUGGACACUUCUGUGGCGUGGCAGAAAUGAAAUCUGCUGUGGACUACAACACAUGUGCAGGUGUGUGGUCCCAGGACAAAUGGAAGGGUCGUUUUGAUGUCAGGUGGAUUUUUGUGAAGGACGUUCCCAAUAGCCAACUGCGACACAUUCGCCUAGAGAACAACGAGAAUAAACCAGUGACCAACUCUAGGGACACUCAGGAAGUGCCUCUGGAAAAGGCUAAGCAGGUGUUGAAAAUUAUAGCCAGCUACAAGCACACCACUUCCAUUUUUGAUGACUUCUCACACUAUGAGAAACGCCAAGAGGAAGAAGAAAGUGUUAAAAAGGAACGUCAAGGUCGUGGGAAAUAAAAGGCAGUUCUACACAGACUGCAGCAACGGUUGCAUCUGCAUAUCCUAAGAGGAAAAAAUGACCUUCAAGAGAAUUAGGACUUUUUUCUUAAUUUCACUGACUUCAGAGACGAUUGCAGACUUGCAGUUUAAGUAUUGGAAUUUCACAAAAGACAUAGGACUUAACUGGAAAAUGAAAAAAAAAAGAAAAAGAAAAAACUAAACAAAAAAUCCCUCUAGGUAGUUUAGGUGAAAAAUGUCCCUUUUAUUUUGGCUUUGGUUGUGAUUUCAGAGCAUAAUGCUAUGUUUUUUUGUCUUUUUACUAUGUUUUUCGGAUUUUUAAGUCCGUAAGUGCAUACAGUUUUCUCUAAUUUUUAAACCCUUUCCUCCUCCCAUUUUGACAUUUGCACUUGGAGAACACUUGAGUUGUGAAGGUUUUGGGCAUCCACCCCAGAAAGUGGGAAUUUGAUUUUAUCCUUCCGAACUGGAAGAACAUUUUUAUGAAGAAUUUUUGUCUAGGAGAAUAUAACAGUGUUACCCAAGGUUGUGUCUUUAAGGGUGGUUCAUUUUCUCUGACCUUUUGUUACUCAAAGUAAAGUACUAGGAGUCCUAAGAAAUGUUCUGUUCUUGUACAUUAUACUGAUUAAGUCAGGAUUAAUUUGAUUUCAAAGCUGAGAACAGUGGUAAAAACUCGUUUACAGAAAUGCAUUUUGGAAGAGAAAAAUACUGUAAAACGUGUCGUGAAUGUUUCUUCAGUUUCUUGUUCAGCCAAUGAGGAAAGGGCAUUGCCUUUCUUUUUACCAUUAAUCACUUCUCAAUAAACGUGAGAUCCUGUUGAGCAUCA